ACUUCCGGCGGCGCGCUGCAGGCGCGGGGAACACCAAUGGCGGGGUACUUGAAGCUGGUGUGUGUUUCCUUUCAGCGUCAAGGGUUCCACACUGUUGGGAGUCGCUGCAAGAAUCGGACAGGCGCUGAGCACCUGUGGCUGACCCGACAUCUCAGGGACCCAUUUGUGAAGGCUGCGAAGGUGGAGAGUUACCGGUGUCGAAGCGCCUUCAAGCUCCUGGAGGUGAACGAGAGGCACCAGAUUCUGCGGCCCGGCCUUCGGGUGUUAGACUGUGGGGCAGCUCCUGGGGCCUGGAGUCAGGUGGCGGUGCAGAAGGUCAACGCCGCAGGCACAGAUCCCAGCUCUCCUGUUGGCUUCGUGCUUGGGGUAGAUCUUCUUCACAUAUUCCCCCUGGAAGGAGCAACUUUUCUGUGCCCUGCUGACGUGACUGACCCGAGAACCUCACAGAGAAUCCUCGAGGUGCUUCCUGGCAGGAGAGCAGAUGUGAUUCUGAGCGACAUGGCGCCCAAUGCCACAGGGUUCCGGGACCUCGAUCAUGACAGGCUCAUCAGCCUGUGCCUGACCCUUCUCAGCGUGACCCCAGACAUCCUGCAACCUGGGGGGACAUUCCUUUGUAAAACCUGGGCUGGAAGUCAAAGCCGUCGGUUACAGAGGAGACUGACAGAGGAAUUCCAGAAUGUAAGGAUCAUCAAACCUGAAGCCAGCAGGAAAGAGUCAUCAGAAGUGUACUUCUUGGCCACACAGUACCACGGAAGGAAGGGCACUGUGAAGCAGUGAGGAUUUCUUGUGCCAUUUUCAUAAUGGUCAUUAGCUCCUUUUAAGCUAGAAACGUAGCCUGAGCUCCUGAAGAGUUCCUGGGAGAUUUGAGCUGAUUUUGGAGAUGGAGCAGGACAAGUGGGGAGUCUCUCUCUCUCUUUCUCUCUCUCUCUUUUUAACCAAAAAGAGAUGACAAAACUAAGUUCAGGGGCCAUGGAAAAUGAAAAAGUCCGCUAUAUUGUGAUUUGGGAAGAGAAAGUUAUCAAGAGAAAGAGGUGAGGAUGGAAGGAUGGAGAAAAACAGACUGUGGGAAGGAUCAGAAGGAAUCCGCCGAGGCAGGGAUGGGUGUGCCCAUGUGUGCCUUGACGGGACUUCAUCUUAUAGACUGUUAAACUGUCACACACAAACAGGCUUUCCACCCCUGCUCUGAGAGCACCACGCACAGAUUUCCAGUUCUUAGUGUGGCUGUUUAAAGUAGAAAAUCUGGGGGCUGGGUGAGGCCACUCAUGCCUGUAAACCCAGGGCUUUAGAAGGCUGAGGCUGGGGGAUUGCUUGAAGUCAGGAGUUCAAGACCAACCUGGGCAACAUAGCAACACCCCCCAUGUCUACAAAAAUGAAAAACCAAAAAGCAAACCAAAAGAAAAAUCUGAAAUUUCCAUCUGGGGAUUAACUUCUGUCUUUCUGGUGAACAAUAUAGCAAUUCACGCAUUCUUCAAGCAGCAAAAGUUCCCGGAACAAUUAGGGAAGACGUAUGGUCUGAAUUUAUCCAGGCAGUGGGUCUGCUUUGGUUUUUGCUGGAAAUUUAUAUCAGUGUCUGGGCUCCCAAGAACAUAAAUGUAAUUGCCAAAGCAAGCAGUGAUGUGGUGUGUUUAUUUUCUUUUACUCAUCUAGGAACUUGACGCAGCUUUAUAUUUAAUAAAAUAAUAGAGAUUGCAUUAUUUUAAGGUA